AUACACAGGGAGGCCAGGCAGCCUGGAGUUAGUCGACCGUUGCGAGACGUUGAGCUGCGGCAGAUGAGUCCAAAGCCGAGAGCCUCGGGACCUCCGGCCAAGGCCAAGGAGACAGGAAAGAGGAAGUCCUCCUCUCAGCCGAGCCCCAGUGGCCCGAAGAAGAAGACUACCAAGGUGGCCGAGAAGGGAGAAGCAGUUCGUGGAGGGAGACGCGGGAAGAAAGGGGCUGCGACAAAGAUGGCGGCCGUGACGGCACCUGAGGCGGAGAGCGGGCCAGCGGCACCCGGCCCCAGCGACCAGCCCAGCCAGGAGCUCCCUCAGCACGAGCUGCCGCCGGAGGAGCCAGUGAGCGAGGGGACCCAGCACGACCCCCUGAGUCAGGAGAGCGAGCUGGAGGAACCACUGAGUAAGGGGCGCCCAUCUACUCCCCUAUCUCCCUGAGCAGCAACUAAGUUUAGGCCCAGCUGCCAGACCUCAGAGAUCUCACCAGCAGGGUGCUUCCCAUGUUGAUGACAAUAAAAUGAAUGUGUUGCAAACCGA